AUUUGUAUAAUUGUGAGCUUGGUAGAGGCAUCAUUGCAGAUCUGCUACUAACUCGGCAUGGCCAGCUCGACAGAGAGCCAGUUUGUUAAACAGCUUGGUGGGGGAGUUCAUCCGUCUUGAUGUUGCCCUGAAUCUACAACUUCAUAUUCAAUAUGCUAAAUAAUCCUCUUUUCUUUUCGUGUGAUUCAUGAUAGUGUCAUCCUCAUCAAGCUUUAUCUUUCUCAUUUCUUGCAAUUUUCUCUUAAGGACUUGCACACGAAGUCUGUAUGUCCGUAGGGCUUUGUACAUCACUCUUGCAAAAGGACUCUCUUCGUCUUGCUUUCAGACUUCUUCAGGUCACAAUGUAAAAGGUGUUUCUUAUUGUGGAUCACAGCUGAAGAAUUUUGAAGCUGCUCAGCUAAAGGACUUUCCCUCUGCGAAGCUGUGAUUCUCUGAAGUGGCCAAAGAAAUUAUGCAGUAAGACCCUUUCCAGUUUUCAUCCUGGGUGUUUCUGAACAGGAACAUAUCUCAUUGAAGUAUUUGCACCUCUACCUACAGACAAGGAAAAGGCUUGGAGCACCUCCAUUCAUUGUGCCAACAGGACCUGAAUGACCGAUUGUUUCUUGCUUACUACUUGUGGUCAACUAAGUAGAGAUUCAUAAGACCUUUAUAGAACCACUGACAACACUGUGACCAAGGAAACUUCCAUCGAUAGAAGAGUGGCUGUGACCCGAAGGAAUGUCUGACCCCCACAGCAGUCCUCUCCUGCCAGAGCCACUUUCCAGCAGAUACAAACUCUACGAGGCAGAGUUUACCAGCCCGAGCUGGCCCUCGACAUCCCCGGAUACUCACCCAGCUCUGCCCCUCCUGGAAAUGCCUGAAGAAAAGGAUCUCCGGUCUUCCAAUGAAGACAGUCACAUUGUGAAGAUCGAAAAGCUCAAUGAAAGGAGUAAAAGGAAAGACGACGGGGUGGCCCAUCGGGACUCAGCAGGCCAAAGGUGCAUCUGCCUCUCCAAAGCAGUGGGCUACCUCACGGGCGACAUGAAGGAGUACAGGAUCUGGCUGAAAGACAAGCACCUUGCCCUCCAGUUCAUAGACUGGGUCCUGAGAGGGACCGCUCAGGUGAUGUUCAUCAACAAUCCUCUCAGCGGCCUCAUCAUCUUCAUAGGGCUGCUGAUCCAGAAUCCCUGGUGGACAAUCACUGGGGGCCUGGGGACAGUGGUCUCGACCUUAACAGCUCUCGCCUUGGGCCAAGACAGGUCUGCCAUUGCCUCAGGACUCCAUGGGUACAACGGGAUGCUGGUGGGACUGCUGAUGGCCGUGUUCUCGGAGAAGUUAGACUACUACUGGUGGCUUCUGUUUCCUGUGACCUUCACAGCCAUGUCCUGCCCAGUUCUUUCUAGUGCCUUGAAUUCCAUCUUCAGCAAGUGGGACCUCCCGGUCUUCACUCUGCCCUUCAACAUUGCAGUCACCUUGUACCUUGCAGCCACAGGCCACUACAACCUCUUCUUCCCCACAACACUGGUAGAGCCUGUGUCUUCAGUGCCCAAUAUCACCUGGACAGAGAUGGAAAUGCCCCUGCUGUUACAAGCCAUCCCUGUUGGGGUCGGCCAGGUGUAUGGCUGUGACAAUCCCUGGACAGGCGGCGUGUUCCUGGUGGCUCUGUUCAUCUCCUCGCCACUCAUCUGCUUGCAUGCAGCCAUUGGCUCAAUCGUGGGGCUGCUAGCAGCCCUGUCAGUGGCCACACCCUUCGAGACCAUCUACACAGGCCUCUGGAGCUACAACUGCGUCCUCUCCUGCAUCGCCAUCGGAGGCAUGUUCUAUGCCCUCACCUGGCAGACUCACCUGCUGGCCCUCAUCUGUGCCCUGUUCUGUGCAUACAUGGAAGCAGCCAUCUCCAACAUCAUGUCAGUGGUGGGCGUGCCACCAGGCACCUGGGCCUUCUGCCUUGCCACCAUCAUCUUCCUGCUCCUGACGACAAACAACCCAGCCAUCUUCAGACUCCCACUCAGCAAAGUCACCUACCCCGAGGCCAACCGCAUCUACUACCUGACAGUGAAAAGCGGUGAAGAAGAGAAGGCCCCCAGCGGAGGCGGUGGGGAGCAUCCACCCACAGCAGGCCCAAAGGUGGAGGAGGGCUCGGAGGCUGUGCUCUCCAAGCACAGGAGUGUAUUUCACAUCGAGUGGUCAUCCAUUCGGAGGAGGAGCAAAGUGUUUGGAAAAGGCGAACACCAGGAAAGACAAAACAAAGACCCAUUUCCCUAUCGAUACCGGAAGCCCACAGUCGAGCUGCUUGAUCUGGACACCAUGGAGGAGAGCUCUGAGAUAAAAGUGGAAACAAACAUUUCCAAGACAUCCUGGAUUCGGAGUUCCAUGGCUGCCAGUGGGAAAAGGGUCAGCAAAGCCCUCAGCUACAUCACAGGAGAGAUGAAGGAGUGUGGAGAGGGACUUAAAGACAAGUCCCCAGUGUUCCAGUUCUUUGACUGGGUCCUCCGAGGCACAUCUCAAGUGAUGUUUGUGAACAACCCCCUCAGCGGCAUCCUCAUCAUCCUCGGCCUCUUCAUCCAGAACCCCUGGUGGGCGAUCUCAGGCUGCCUGGGUACCAUCAUGUCCACCUUGACAGCCCUCAUCCUGAGUCAGGACAAGUCGGCCAUCGCUGCAGGAUUUCACGGCUACAAUGGGGUGCUGGUGGGGCUGCUGAUGGCCGUGUUCUCAGACAAAGGUGACUACUACUGGUGGCUGUUGCUACCCGUCAUCAUCAUGUCCAUGUCUUGCCCCAUCCUCUCCAGUGCCCUGGGUACCAUCUUCAGCAAGUGGGACCUCCCAGUCUUCACACUGCCCUUCAAUAUCACUGUGACUUUGUACCUGGCAGCCACGGGCCACUACAACCUUUUCUUCCCCACAACGCUGCUGCAGCCUGCAUCCGCCAUGCCCAACAUCACCUGGUCAGAGGUCCAAGUGCCCUUGCUUUUGAGAGCCAUCCCCGUUGGAAUUGGCCAAGUGUACGGCUGUGAUAACCCCUGGACUGGAGGCAUCUUCCUCAUAGCUCUGUUCAUAUCCUCACCUCUCAUUUGCUUGCAUGCAGCAAUUGGAUCCACCAUGGGGAUGCUAGCAGCACUCACUAUUGCGACGCCCUUUGACUCCAUCUACUUCGGCCUGUGUGGCUUCAACAGCACCCUCGCAUGCAUAGCGAUAGGAGGCAUGUUCUACGUCAUCACCUGGCAGACGCACCUCCUCGCCAUCGCCUGCGCACUGUUUGCUGCCUACCUGGGUGCUGCCCUGGCUAACAUGUUAUCUGUGUUUGGAUUGCCGCCCUGCACUUGGCCCUUCUGUCUCUCAGCUCUCACCUUCCUGCUCCUGACGACCAAUAACCCCGCCAUCUACAAGCUCCCGCUCAGCAAAGUCACCUACCCAGAGGCCAACCGCAUCUACUACCUGUCCCAGGAGAGAAACAGAAGGGCAUCAAUCAUAACAAAGUAUCAGGCCUACGAUGUCUCCUAAGUUUCCCUGUCUAAAACACAUCAGUGUAAAUUCAGGCUUCAGCACGCCGUCCAGAUCCCCAGGAUAAGAGACCACUUAGCCUUCCCUUUGGUCUGUUCUGUGACUCUCUCCCCAAACACAAAGAAGCGUGUAUGUAGUCACCAUUCCAGAACCUCUCUUUUCUAAGAUGCACAACACUUAUCAAAGAUAUGUUUAGUUUAGACUUUAUACCCUUAGCUUUCCCAUAAGAGCUCCCUUUGUGGGGAACUUGCCCUCUUCUGCGAAAUAAGCCUCAUCCUUAAAGAGAAGUCACCGGCCGGGCACGGUGGCUCACGCCUGUAAUCCCAGCACUUUGGGAGGCCGAGGCGGGUGGAUCACGAGGUCAGGAGAUCGAGACCAUCCUGGCGAACAUGGUGAGACCCCAUCUCUACUAAAAAUACAAAAAAUUAGCCAGGCAUGGUGGCGGGCACCUGUAGUCCCAGCUACUUGGGAGGCUGAGGCAGGAGAAUGGCGUGAACCCGGGAGGUGGAGCUUGCAGUGAGCCAAGAUCACGCCACUGCACUCCAGCCUGGGCAACGGAGUGAGACUCUGUCUCAAAAAAAAAAAAAAGGGGAAGUCACCAAGAAAGGGAUAGAGGUCAGUGACAUGGUCAUCACACAACUCGGUCAUUUAAUAUGGCAAAACACAAUACCAAGAACUGUGCAUUAGCCCGGAAGGCAAGAGGGUUGGUUCUGCCCCAGCUCUGCUGCUAAUGAGCCCCUACCAGGUUGAGCAAGUCUUUCCCCACUCUCCACCUCCAUUUCUUAAUCAGUUUCAUGACAGGGAAGGAUUUGAAAGUCCUUUCCACCUCAGAAGUGUUGAUUAUUCUCUCUCUCCUAUAAUCUGAUGAAAUCAGCAUGACAACAAGUAAUUUAAGUAAAGGACAGAAGGGUUACCCAAGAAGAGGCAGGAAAAUGUUAACGUUCUAUAAAGUUUUAUUCUUGAGUCAUAGGAAAAUGCUCUCCAGACGUGGGGUUAGGAACCUAAAUUCACUGAAAAUGCCAAUGUGCUUUCCUUUACAUUACAGAAAUAUUUCUGGAAGUGUCAGAUGAAAACUGAUCUUUAUCAACACUCAAAUCAUAUUAUAAACAAAUGUGUUUCCCUUUGUAAUAUUCAUAAUCAUACUGUCAUUAAACUGUUUAAGUUUGCAA